AGUGGCCGGCUGGGAUCAGCCUUUAAGAUGGCGUCUCCUCAGGGGGGCCAGAUUGCGAUCGCGAUGAGGCUUCGGAACCAGCUCCAGUCAGUGUACAAGAUGGACCCGCUACGGAACGAGGAGGAGGUUCGAGUGAAGAUCAAAGACUUGAAUGAACACAUUGUUUGCUGCCUAUGCGCCGGCUACUUCGUGGAUGCCACCACCAUCACAGAGUGUCUUCAUACUUUCUGCAAGAGUUGUAUUGUGAAGUACCUCCAAACUAGCAAGUACUGCCCCAUGUGCAACAUUAAGAUCCACGAGACACAGCCACUGCUCAACCUCAAACUGGACCGGGUCAUGCAGGACAUCGUGUAUAAGCUGGUGCCUGGCUUGCAAGACAGUGAAGAGAAACGGAUUCGGGAAUUCUACCAGUCCCGAGGUUUGGACCGGGUCACCCAGCCCACUGGGGAAGAGCCAGCACUGAGCAACCUCGGCCUCCCCUUCAGCAGCUUUGACCACUCUAAAGCCCACUACUAUCGCUAUGAUGAGCAGUUGAACCUGUGCCUGGAGCGGCUGAGUUCUGGCAAAGACAAGAAUAAAAGCGUCCUGCAGAACAAGUAUGUCCGAUGUUCUGUUAGAGCUGAGGUACGCCAUCUCCGGAGGGUCCUGUGUCACCGCUUGAUGCUAAACCCUCAGCAUGUGCAGCUCCUUUUUGACAAUGAAGUUCUCCCUGAUCACAUGACAAUGAAGCAGAUAUGGCUCUCCCGCUGGUUCGGCAAGCCAUCCCCUUUGCUUUUACAAUACAGUGUGAAAGAGAAGAGGAGGUAGGGGCCAAGCCCCCACCCCAUCCCACUCCCCUUCCCUCCCCAGAUAUUUAUGUGAAAUGAACUGCAGCUUUAUUUUUUGAAAUAAAAACUUUUAAAAAGCA